ACUCUGCGCUGGGCGCGCGGAGGCCUAGGCGGGAAGCUCGAGCGGCGGCGCCAUGGCCCGAGCGUGGCAGCACCCGUUCCUCAACGUCUUCAGACACUUCCGGGUGGACGAGUGGAAGCGCUCCGCCAAGCAGGGGGACGUGGCCGUGGUCACGGACAAGACCCUGAAGGGCGCCGUGUAUCGCAUUCGGGGCUCAGUCUCUGCCGCCAACUACAUCCAGCUCCCUAAGAGCAGCACCCAGUCUCUGGGGCUGACGGGACGAUACCUGUAUGUGCUCUUUCGGCCCCUGCCCAGCAAGCACUUCGUCAUCCACCUCGAUGUGUCCUCCAAGGACAACCAAGUCAUCCGUGUGUCUUUCUCCAACCUCUUCAAGGAGUUUAAGUCUACGGCCACGUGGCUCCAGUUUCCCUUGGUCCUGGAGGCCAGGACACCUCAGAGAGAUCUGGUGGGUUUGGCCCCCUCCGGAGCCCGCUGGACCUGCCUGCAGCUCGAUCUGCAGGACGUUCUCCUGGUCUACCUGAACCGGUGCUACGGCCAUCUCAAGAGCAUCAGGCUGUGCGCCAGCCUGCUGGUCAGGAACCUGUACACCAGUGACCUGUGCUUUGAGCCUGCCAUCUCUGGGGCCCAGUGGGCAAAGCUGCCCGUGACUCCUAUGCCUCGGGAAAUGGCAUUCCCUGUGCCCAAGGGAGAGAGCUGGCAUGACCGCUACAUCCACGUCCGGUUUCCAAGUGAGAGCUUGAAAGUGCCUUCCAAGCCGAUUGAGAAGAGCUGUUCCCCUCCUGAGGCAGUCCUCCUGGGGCCGGGGCCACAGCCUCUCCCUUGCCCGGUGGCCUCCAGCAAACCUGUGCGGUUCAGUGUGUCUCCAGUGGUCCAGACGCCCAGCCCCACAGCCCAGUCCGGCCGGGCCGCCUUGGCACCCAGGCCCUUCCCGGAGGUCAGCCUGUCCCAAGAGCGCUCAGACGCCUCCAACGCGGAUGGCCCCGGUUUCCAUAGCCUUGAGCCCUGGGCCCAGCUGGAGGCCUCUGACAUCCACACGGCUGCUGCCGGCACCCACGUGUUGACUCACGAGUCGGCUGAGGUGCCCGUGGCCCGCACCGGCUCCUGCGAAGGCUUCCUCCCAGACCCAGUCCUGAGGCUCAAGGGCGUCAUCGGCUUUGGGGGCCACGGCACCAGACAGGCCCUGUGGACCCCAGACGGGGCGGCUGUCGUGUACCCCUGCCAUGCGGUCAUCGUCGUCCUGCUCGUGGACACGGGGGAGCAGCGCUUCUUCCUUGGCCACACAGACAAGGUCUCCGCCCUGGCGCUGGAUGGCAGCAGCUCACUAUUGGCCUCGGCCCAGGCAAGGGCCCCUAGUGUGAUGCGGCUCUGGGACUUCCAGACCGGGCGGUGCUUGUGCCUGUUCCGGAGCCCAAUGCACGUUGUCUGCUCUCUCAGCUUCUCUGACAGCGGGGCCCUUCUCUGCGGGGUUGGCAAGGACCACCACGGGAGGACGAUGGUGGUGGCCUGGGGCACCGGCCAGGUGGGCCUCGGUGGCGAGGUGGUCGUUCUGGCAAAGGCGCACACUGACUUUGACGUCCAGGCCUUCCGGGUCACCUUUUUUGAUGAAACCAGGAUGGCGUCGUGCGGGCAGGGCAGUGUGCGGCUCUGGCGGCUGCGUGGCGGGGUGCUGCGUUCCUGCCCCGUGGACUUAGGGGAGCACCACGCGCUGCAGUUCACCGACCUGGCCUUCAAGCAGGCCCGGGACGGCUGCCCGGAGCCCUCGGCUGCCAUGCUCUUCGUGUGCAGCCGCAGUGGCCACAUCUUGGAGAUUGACUGUCAGCGCAUGGUCGUGCGGCAUGCCCGCCGCCUGCUCCCCACACGGACUCCAGGCGGUCCCCACCCACAGAAGCAGACCUUCAGCUCAGGCCCCGGCAUUGCCAUCAGCAGCCUCAGCGUCUCCCCGGCCAUGUGUGCUGUGGGCUCUGAGGACGGCUUCUUGCGGCUCUGGCCCCUGGACUUCUCCUCGGUGCUCCUGGAGGCAGAGCACGAGGGCCCCGUCAGCUCAGUCUGUGUCAGCCCCGAUGGCCUCCGUGUGCUGUCUGCCACCUCCUCGGGCCACCUGGGCUUCCUGGACACGCUGUCCCGGGUGUACCACAUGCUGGCUCGCUCCCACACCGCCCCGGUGUUGGCCCUCGCCAUGGAGCAGAGGCGGGGACAGCUGGCCACCGUGUCCCAGGACCGUACCGUCCGCAUCUGGGACCUGGCCACCCUGCAGCAGCUAUACGACUUCACAUCAUCAGAGGACGCCCCGUGCGCUGUCACCUUCCACCCCACAAGGCCAACCUUUUUCUGUGGCUUUAGCAGUGGGGCCGUGCGCUCCUUCAGCCUGGAGGCCGCUGAGGUCCUGGUGGAACACACGUGCCACCGAGGAGCUGUCACCGGCCUGACCGCCACCCCUGACGGCCGCCUGCUCUUCAGCUCCUGCUCCCAGGGCUCCCUGGCCCAGUACAGCUGUGCGGACCCCCAGUGGCAUGUCCUCCGAGUGGCAGCGGACAUGGUAUGCCCGGAUGCCCCCGCGAGCCCCAGCGCCCUGGCAGUCAGCAGGGAUGGCCGCCUGCUGGCCUUUGUGGGACCCUCCAGGUGCACAGUGACAGUCAUGGGCUCGGCCUCCCUUGAUGAGCUGCUGCGAGUUGACAUCGGCACUCUGGACCUGGCCAGCAGCCGCCUGGACUCAGCCAUGGCUGUGUGCUUUGGCCCUGCAGCUCUGGGCCACCUGCUGGUGUCCACCUCGUCCAACAGAGUCGUGGUGCUGGAUGCUGUGUCGGGCCGCAUCAUCCGGGAGCUGCCCGGUGUCCACCCUGAGCCCUGCCCCUCCUUGACGCUCAGUGAGGACGCCCGCUUCCUGCUGAUUGCCGCCGGCCGGACCAUCAAGGUGUGGGACUACGCCACACAGGCCAGCCCAGGCCCCCAGGUGUACAUCGGCCACUCGGAACCCGUGCAGGCUGUGGCCUUCUCUCCUGACCAGCAGCAGGUCCUCAGCGCAGGGGACGCCGUCUUCCUCUGGGAUGUCCUGGCCCCUACUGAGAGCGACCAAAGCUUCCCCGGGGCCCCCCCAGCCUGCAAGACAGGCCCGGGCGCAGGACCGCUGGAGGACGCAGCGUCCAGGGCCAGCGAGCUCCCCCGGCAGCAGGUCCCCAAGCCAUGUCAGGCAUCUCCACCACGGCUGGGCGUCUGUGCCAGGCCUCCCGAAGGUGGCGAUGGCGCCAGGGACACCAGGAAUUCGGGGGCCCCACGCACCACCUACCUGGCUUCCUGCAAGGCCUUCACGCCUGCCAGGGUCAGCUGCAGCCCCCACUCUGCCAAGGGCACUUGCCCGCCUCCCGCCAGCGGUGGGUGGCUGCGUCUGAAGGCUGUCGUCGGUUACAGCGGGAAUGGGCGGGCCAACAUGGUCUGGAGGCCGGACACAGGCUUCUUUGCCUACACGUGCGGCCGCCUGGUGGUGGUGGAGGACCUGCACUCUGGCGCCCAGCAGCACUGGUCCGGCCACUCUGCGGAGAUCUCCACGCUGGCCCUCAGCCACAGUGCCCAGGUCCUGGCCUCUGCCUCGGGCCGAAGCAGCACGACCGCCCAUUGUCAGAUCCGCGUCUGGGACGUGUCUGGCGGCCUCUGCCAGCAUCUCAUUUUCCCCCAUAGCACCACCGUGCUGGCCCUGGCCUUCUCACCAGAUGACAGGCUUCUUGUCACACUGGGGGACCACGAUGGCCGCACCCUCGCCCUGUGGGGCACGGCCACCUAUGACCUCGUGUCCUCCACCCGCCUCCCGGAGCCGGUGCAUGGUGUGGCCUUCAACCCCUGGGACGCCGGCGAGCUCACCUGUGUGGGCCAGGGCACUGUCACCUUCUGGCUCCUUCAGCAGCGUGGGGCAGACAUCAGCCUUCAGGUGCGUCGAGAGCCAGUCCCAGAGGCAGUGGGGGCUGGAGAGCUGACCUCGCUCUGCUACGGGGCACCUCCCCUGCUCUAUUGUGGCACCAGCUCUGGCCAGGUCUGUGUCUGGGACACGCGUGCCGGCCGCUGCUUCUUGUCCUGGGAGGCGGAUGACGGUGGCAUUGGGCUGUUGCUGUUCUCGGGUUCUCGAUUGGUCAGCGGCAGCAGCACGGGGCGGCUGCGCCUGUGGGCCGUGGGGGCUGUGUCGGAGCUGAGGUGCAAGGGCUCAGGCGCCAGGUCCAGUUCUGUGUUCAUGGAACACGAGCUGGUGCUGGACGGGGCUGUGGUGAGUGCCAGCUUCGAUGACAGCGUGGACAUGGGCGUCGUGGGCACCACGGCGGGCACGCUGUGGUUUGUCAGCUGGGCCGAGGGCACCAGCACACGUCUCAUCAGUGGCCACAGGAGCAAGAAAUCACAUCAGUCCGGGCGUGGUGGUUCAUGCCUGUGAUCCCAGCACUCUGGGAGGCCAAGGCAGGUGGAUCACCUGAGGUCAGGAGUUCGAGACCAGCCUGGUCAACAUGGCGAAAUCCCAUCUCUACUGAAAAUACAAAAAUUAGCCGGGCCUCUUGAUGUAUACCUGUAAUCCCAGCUACUCUGGAGGCUGAGACAAGAGAAUCGCUUGAACCCAGGAGGCAGAGGUUGCAGUGAACCAAGAUUGCACCACUGCACUCCAGCCUGGGCGACAGAGACUCCAUCUCAAAGGAAAAAAAAAAGAUGAAAAACCCCACAUCGUCUGUCCCUGCACCUCCCAUAGACUGGCUUUGCUGACUCAGUCUCAUGGGAUUGUUCUCUGAGGCUCAAGAGGUCAGGAGGCCCAGGUAGCUACUGGGUCAAGUUCUGCUCUCUCUGGGUCAGGUCUGUUCAGGUUCUGGUUGGUGUUGGGUCUAGUCCUGUAAGGCCCAGCUCUGGCCUGCAGCCUCCUGGUGCUGGAGCUGCGUCUCCAAGAAGUACACAGCACUCAUCUCUCUGGGACCUCCUGGUCUGGAAGCUCUGUGGCCUCAUGGGGUUGGGACAGCCACCGUGUCGCCCCCUCACCCGCCAGCUGCAGCCUUAGGAGAGGUGGCCUCCUGGGCGGAAUUGGGGCGGCAGGACAGGUGCCAUUCCUUCCCCUGCUGGACCAGGUUCCUGGCGUGGCGUUGGUCUAGCAGCUGUGGCCAUGGGCUUCCUCCUGUGGGUGUAAGAGCUCUGCGUGUGGUCAGCUGGGCCCCACGGGAUUGAUUUUUCCUUGAUGCUGAGUCCCAUCAUCCAGUUGCCCCUGGGUUGUUUCUUUAGAAACCUGUCUUUAGUAUUUGGAGAUGACGAUAGCCAGCAAAGAAAGUUGAGUUUGAGACAGGUGAGGGUUGUUUACUUUUCUGGAAGCAGGUUUGCUGAGGUGUAGUCGUCACAGCACAAGCUCCGUGUGUUUCAGGGGGUGGCUUUUGGCAUAUUCAGCAGCUUUGGAAACCCCGUGCGUGCCUAGAGGAAACCCCGUGCGUGCCUGUUCCUCGGUCGCUCCCUGCUUCCCGCCUCCCCAGCCCCUGGCGACCGUUGAGUGGCUUUCUGUGUCUGGGUCUUCCCAUUCAGGAUAUUCUGUAGGAACUGGCUCACCUGGCUUCUCACCCUGAGCAUGGUUUCCAGGGUCAUCCCAGCCGCUGUGUGUGCCAAGCCAGUCAUCCCUCUUGAUGGCCAAAUACUGUUCCAUUGUACGGAUAGAUCAUGUGUGUGUCCAUCCACCAGGGCUGGGAAAUUCGGGUCCUGAGACCGUGACCUGAGCCCGUGGUCACUGGUGGCCUUCCUGUGAUGUGGAAGUGCGAGGAAUUCUGGGCCCCGCCUGUGUGGUUCUGCCUGGGCGGUUCUGCCUGGGCCUGGACUUUGCCGUUUCCUUGUAGGGCCCAGGGCCCUCCCGGGGAGAUGGACUGAGCUGUCCUGGUCUGAGUCCCUGCAGUCCCUCAUUGCUCAGCUGAACUGAAUUUUUUUUUUUUUUUUGAGACGGAGUUUCUUGUCGCCCAGGCUGGAGUGCAGUGGCAUGAUCUUGGCUCACUGCAAGCUCCGCCUCCCGGGUUCACACCAUUCUCCUGUCUCAGCCUCCCAAGUAGCUGGGACUACAGGCACCCGCCACCACGCCCGACUAAUUUUUUGUAUUUUUAGUAGAGUCGGGGUUUCACCGUGUUAGCCAGGAUGGUCUCGAACUCCUGACCCCGUGAUCCGCCCACCUUGGCCUCCCAAAGGGCUGGGAUUACAGGCAUGAGCCACCGCGCCCGGCUGAACUGAUUUUUUUUUAAUGAAGUGCAUCGUGUUCCCACUUGCACUUAAAGUUCACAUUUGGUGCCAGGCUGUAUUGCUUCUUCUCACUGGUGAGUGGCAGCUGUGUCUCCUUUCUGCCAGUCCAGCAGUCCCAGCUGUCAGUGGCACCUGCAUAAUGACACGUCUGCAUUUCCCCCCAAUCAGCGUGCAGCGGUUUUGGGAGGAGGAAUGCGACUGCAUGGCGCGCUCGCUGCAACCUCAGUCUGCAGCCUGCUAGGGACGCACGGCCACACUCCUGUCUUUCAGCCUCAGUCUGCAGCCUGCUAGGGACGCACGGCCACACUCCUGUCUUUCAGCCUCAGUCUGCAGCCUGCUAGGGACGCACGGCCACACUCCUGUCUUUCAGCCUCAGUCUGUAGCCUGCUAGGGAUGCACGGCCACGCUCCUGUCUUUGAGGUGCUGUCAGAACAGCUUUCUCCUCGGUAUCCCGCCGGGUUUGACUGGCUAGUGGGCUUGCUUUGGUUUGGACUCACCCAGAUCUAGUGCAGGGACACACACGGGGGCCGGCAUUGCUCCUUUCCGCCAUGUGGAGUUGGCCGGGGCCAGAGGCACAU